AGGCCGGAAGGAGGCUGCCGGAGGGCGGGAGGCAGGAGCGGGCCAGGAGCUGCUGGGCUGGAGCGGCGGCGCCGCCAUGUCCGACAGCGAGAAGCUCAACCUGGACUCGAUCAUCGGGCGCCUGCUGGAAGGGUCCAGGGUCCUGACACCCCAUUGCGCCCCAGUGCAGGGCUCGCGGCCUGGCAAGAAUGUACAGCUGACAGAGAACGAGAUCCGCGGUCUGUGCCUGAAAUCCCGGGAGAUUUUUCUGAGCCAGCCCAUUCUUCUGGAGCUGGAGGCACCCCUCAAGAUCUGCGGUGACAUACACGGCCAGUACUACGACCUUCUGCGACUAUUUGAGUAUGGCGGUUUCCCUCCCGAGAGCAACUACCUCUUUCUGGGGGACUAUGUGGACAGGGGCAAGCAGUCCUUGGAGACCAUCUGCCUGCUGCUGGCCUAUAAGAUCAAGUACCCCGAGAACUUCUUCCUGCUCCGUGGGAACCACGAGUGUGCCAGCAUCAACCGCAUCUAUGGUUUCUACGAUGAGUGCAAGAGACGCUACAACAUCAAACUGUGGAAAACCUUCACUGACUGCUUCAACUGCCUGCCCAUCGCGGCCAUAGUGGACGAAAAGAUCUUCUGCUGCCACGGAGGCCUGUCCCCGGACCUGCAGUCUAUGGAGCAGAUUCGGCGGAUCAUGCGGCCCACAGAUGUGCCUGACCAGGGCCUGCUGUGUGACCUGCUGUGGUCUGACCCUGACAAGGACGUGCAGGGCUGGGGCGAGAACGACCGUGGCGUCUCUUUUACCUUUGGAGCCGAGGUGGUGGCCAAGUUCCUCCACAAGCACGACUUGGACCUCAUCUGCCGAGCACACCAGGUGGUAGAAGACGGCUACGAGUUCUUUGCCAAGCGGCAGCUGGUGACACUUUUCUCAGCUCCCAACUACUGUGGCGAGUUUGACAAUGCUGGCGCCAUGAUGAGUGUGGACGAGACCCUCAUGUGCUCUUUCCAGAUCCUCAAGCCCGCCGACAAGAACAAGGGGAAGUACGGGCAGUUCAGUGGCCUGAACCCUGGAGGCCGACCCAUCACCCCACCCCGCAAUUCCGCCAAAGCCAAGAAAUAGCCCCCGCACACCACCCUGUGCCCCAGAUGAUGGAUUGAUUGUACAGAAAUCAUGCUGCCAUGCUGGGGGGGGGUCACCCCGACCCCUCAGGCCCACCUGUCACGGGGAACAUGGAGCCUUGGUGUAUUUUUCUUUUCUUUUUUUAAUGAAUCAAUAGCAGCGUCCAGUCCCCCAGGGCUGCUUCCUGCCUGCACCUGCGGUGACUGUGAGCAGGAUCCUGGGGCCGAGGCUGCAGCUCAGGGCAACGGCAGGCCAGGUCGUGGGUCUCCAGCCGUGCUUGGCCUCAGGGCUGGCAGCCGGAUCCUGGGGCAACCCAUCUGGUCUCUUGAAUAAAGGUCAAAGCUGGAUUCUC